GCUUCCGGCCUCACACCUGCCAAGCAUCACACCUGCCAAGCAUCACACCUGCCAAGCAUCACACCUGCCAAGCAUCACACCUGCGAUGCCUGCACGAGCUGGGUGCGGUCCGCGCAGCUGCAGUAAGGGGGCGACCCGGCGUCUGUUAGUCGGCGGUUCAUCUCCUUCGUGCCUCGAUGAGCUUUAACGCCAUUUUCCUCCAUUCUCUUUCUUCACCUCUUGAGUGAGUGGCCAUGAGCUGGGCUGCAAGAGUCCUGGGGAGCAGCCAGAGAGCGGGCGCCGCGGGAGCGAAUUGUUUUUGCCCAAGGAUGGUUCUGUGUCUCCGCCAGGCGGCAUGUGACCUGCUCGGGCGCGGGUGGCCCUUCACCCCUGUGAGUGUGGCCAGAAGUACCUCUCACCUGGACCUGCGGACCCCGGGCGCAGUCCUGGAGCUGAGAACUGGAGGUUGGGGGAACAGCAGGGUAAAGGGGAGAGAAAAGGGGGUCAGCUGCGGGACGGAGUGCCGUCCCAGCUGUAGUUUCAUGUUUGGUGGAGCAACCCCUGUUCCUUUCCUCUCUCUCUCUCUUAAUUCCUCUUAACUGUACUCACGCUUCCUUCUCCUUCCCCUGGUCCGCUUCAUGGAUGCUGAGCUGCCUGGCCAGAACCUACCCAGCUUCUUUGCUGGUCAGAUUUGUCGGUCUUUUGUGUGUCUGCAGCACCUCCUUCCACACGGGCCCAGGAGUUCUCUAUACGCGCUCUCACCGCAGGUCUUGGAAUUCCAAGCCAUUUCCAAUUCCAGGUCUUGGAAAUGGCUGUGCAAUUUGUCUUCACUGUUAGGUUUCCAAGAUGGCAACUAUCAAGAGUGAACUUAUUAAGAAUUUCGCGGAAGAGGAGGCCAUUCAUCACAAUAAGAUCUCCAUUGUAGGAACUGGAUCGGUUGGUGUGGCUUGUGCUAUCAGCAUCUUAUUAAAAGGUUUGAGUGAUGAACUUGUCCUUGUGGAUGUUGAUGAAGGCAAACUGAAGGGUGAGACAAUGGAUCUUCAACAUGGCAGCCCUUUUAUGAAAAUGCCAAAUAUUGUCUCCAGCAAAGAUUACCUGGUCACUGCAAACUCCAAUCUAGUGAUUAUCACAGCAGGUGCACGCCAGAAAAAAGGAGAAACACGCCUUGAUUUAGUCCAGCGAAAUGUAUCCAUCUUUAAAUUAAUGAUUCCCAAUAUUACCCAGUACAGUCCUCACUGCAAACUGCUUAUUGUUACUAAUCCAGUGGAUAUCUUAACUUAUGUAGCCUGGAAGUUGAGUGGAUUUCCCAAAAACCGUGUUAUUGGAAGUGGUUGUAAUCUGGACUCUGCUCGUUUUCGUUACUUUAUUGGGCAAAGGCUUGGCAUCCACUCUGAAAGCUGUCAUGGGCUGAUCCUUGGAGAGCAUGGCGACUCAAGUGUUCCUGUGUGGAGUGGUGUGAACAUUGCUGGCGUCCCUCUGAAGGAUCUGAACCCAGAUAUAGGAACUGAUAAAGAUCCUGAGCAGUGGGAAAAUGUCCACAAAAAAGUGAUUUCCAGUGGCUAUGAGAUGGUCAAAAUGAAAGGUUAUACUUCUUGGGGCAUUAGCCUAUCUGUAGCUGAUUUAACAGAAAGUAUUUUGAAGAAUCUUAGGAGAGUGCAUCCAGUUUCUACCCUAAGUAAGGGCCUCUAUGGAAUAAAUGAAGACAUAUUCCUUAGUGUCCCAUGUAUCCUGGGAGAGAAUGGUAUCACAGACCUCAUAAAAGUAAAACUGACUCUUGAAGAGGAGGCCUGCUUGCAAAAGAGUGCAGAAACACUUUGGGAAAUUCAGAAGGAGCUCAAGCUUUAAAGUUGCUUAAAGCUAAUUCUGUAGAUUGAAGAUGAAAUAGUAGUUAUGGAAUUGUAUAUGUCAAACUUUUGAAUAAAUUUGAAUUUCUAAAAGUUGGAAAAAUAGAGGAAAGAGUGACCUAUUUAGUAUAGCCUUCCAGCUUUUUUUUUUUUCUUUUUUGGGAGGGUCUCAUUCUGUCACCCAGGCUGGAGUGCAGUGGCACAAUCAUGGCUCACUGCAACCUUGACCUCCCGAGCUCAGGUGAGCCUCCCACUUCAGCCUCCAGAGUAGGUGGGACCACAUGCGUGUGCCUCCAUGCCUGCCUAAUUUUUGUAUCUUUUUGUAGAGAUGGGGUUUUGCCAUGUCAUCCAAGCUGGUUUUGAACUCCCAAAGUGCUGAGAUUACAGGGGUGAGCCACUGUGCCUGGCCUUAGCUUUGAUUUAGUAUCCAGAUGAUAGAUGACACUUUUUUUUUUUUUUUUUUAAAGUGACGGCAUCAAAGAUGUUUUUGGUACUUCUCAGUACUUGCCUUGUAUGUAUACGUAAUUGCCAUCUGGUCCACAAGAAUGUGUUUACUGUGUUACACAAAUCCUGAUUCUUUUCAUCAGGUGCAUAGUAAUUCUUCUCUAUGGCUUAAUACCUAUGUUCAUUUACAUGCUAUCUCUACAAUGUAAAAAUAAAAGUGUAUAUAUAUACACACACACACAGAGAGUAAUCUAAAUGUUCCUAACACUAGAUAAAACAUUGAUUUGA